GUAGGUUGCAAAAAUUUUCUCCCAUUUUGUAGUUGUGUUCACACAUUUGUCCGAAUGGUAAGCAAAACAUUUCCUCCUGUAGCUUAACAUAGCCCUUAUUUAAAAGUAAAUAGCUGCAGGCGAAUAUAGGUUUGUAGAUUUUGUUGUGAUUUAAACACAAAUAAGAGAGAUUUCAAUGUAGUCGUCCGGGGAUAGGUGGGAGACUAAAAUUGGGAAGGGAUUCCCAAUGAAGGGUUUAAUACAAAACGAAAUUAAAUAUUUUUUGCACAGGUUCCAUACAAGUAAAUCCGAAAAAAAGUGGAGGGGGAGGGGGUCGUCCACACCGCGAAUUGUUAUGGCGAGGAAGAUAAAUGUAUUACUAAAGAAGACAUGGACAGAAGGUGGAUGGCGCUGCGGCCUGGCUCCCGCAGACGGACUGCCUUCUUCUUCCAUUCGAGAUCGCUCGUACCGAACCUCCUUGCCUUCUUCCUGGGUCUCUCGGGGGCUGGACCAAUACAUCUGCCGAUGCCCUGGCCGAAUGGCAGGCGACGUCGGGUCCUGGACCCCCACACGCAGCUCAGUACCCACGAGGCCCCAGGCUGCUGGAAGCCUGUAGCUCUGCCGGGGAUGAAAGCCUGUCCGCAGUUUCUGCUGGAGUGGUCAGCCUCUGCCGGAAGGGGGCGCCCUUGUCUUUUUAAUGGUCCUAGCACACUAGUGGAAUAAAUCUCUCAGAUUCCACAUCUUUUGUUUGCUCUGAAUUUAUUGCGAGUGAAAAACAGAGAAAACCCUCAAGUUUCAGUUUCUGAUAGCAGAGUGUGGGAGUUAGAGCAUGGGGACUCCAGAGGUCCCAGACCCCCAAAGGUCUCUACCAGGGCCAUCUCCGUUAGUGGCCAUGGCAGCCCCUCUUGUGGCCUUUUUCCUGCAUCACCAAGUCAAUC